AGAACCGCGACCUCCGCAACCUUGAGCGGCAUCCGUGGAGUGCGCCUGCGCAGCUACGACCGCAGCAGGAAAGCGCCGCCGGCCAGGCCCAGCUGUGGCCGGACAGGGACUGGAAGAGAGGACGCGGUCGAGUAGGUGUGCACCAGCCCUGGCAACGAGAGCGUCUACCCCGAACUCUGCUGGCCUUGAGGUGGGGAAGCCGGGGAGGGCAGUUGAGGACCCCGCGGAGGCGCGUGACUGGUUGAGCGGGCAGGCCAGCCUCCGAGCCGGGUGGACACAGCUCCUACAGCUCUGGACAGGCUGCUUUUCAUUUUGGUGAGUCCAUCCAGUACCUCCACGUGCCCUGUUUUUCUCCAGGCACAUCCUUGGCCUCUUCCACAGUCCUUGGGUUUUAAAACAUGAAUCCUACACUCAUCCUUGCUGCCUUUUGCCUGGGAAUUGCCUCAGCUACUCUAACAUUUGAUCACAGUUUAGAGGCACAGUGGACCAAGUGGAAGGCGAUGCACAACAGAUUAUACGGCAUGAAUGAAGAAGGAUGGAGGAGAGCAGUGUGGGAGAAGAACAUGAAGAUGAUUGAACUGCACAAUCAGGAAUACAGGGAAGGGAAACACAGCUUCACAAUGGCCAUGAACGCCUUUGGAGACAUGACCAGUGAAGAAUUCAGGCAGGUGAUGAAUGGCUUUCAAAACCGUAAGCCCAGGAAGGGGAAAGUGUUCCAGGAACCUCUGUUUUAUGAGGCCCCCAGAUCUGUGGAUUGGAGAGAGAAAGGCUACGUGACUCCUGUGAAGAAUCAGGGUCAGUGUGGUUCUUGUUGGGCUUUUAGUGCUACUGGUGCUCUUGAAGGACAGAUGUUCCGGAAAACUGGGAGGCUUAUCUCACUGAGUGAGCAGAAUCUGGUAGACUGCUCUGGGCCUCAAGGCAAUGAAGGCUGCAAUGGUGGCCUAAUGGAUUAUGCUUUCCAGUAUGUUCAGGAUAAUGGAGGCCUGGACUCUGAGGAAUCCUAUCCAUAUGAGGCAACAGAAGAAUCCUGUAAGUACAAUCCCAAGUAUUCUGUUGCUAAUGACACCGGCUUUGUGGACAUCCCUAAGCAGGAGAAGGCCCUGAUGAAGGCAGUUGCAACUGUGGGGCCCAUUUCUGUUGCUAUUGAUGCAGGUCAUGAGUCCUUCCUGUUCUAUAAAGAAGGCAUUUAUUUUGAGCCAGACUGUAGCAGUGAAGACAUGGAUCAUGGUGUGCUGGUGGUUGGCUACGGAUUUGAAAGCACAGAAUCAGAUAACAAUAAAUAUUGGCUGGUGAAGAACAGCUGGGGUGAAGAAUGGGGCAUGGGUGGCUACGUAAAGAUGGCCAAAGACCGGAGAAACCAUUGUGGAAUUGCCUCAGCAGCCAGCUACCCCACUGUGUGAGCUGGUGGACGGUGAUGAGGAAGGACUUGACUGGGGAUGGCGCAUGCAUGGGAGGAAUUCAUCUUCAGUCUACCAGCCCCCGCUGUGUCGGAUACACACUCGAAUCAUUGAAGAUCCGAGUGUGAUUUGAAUUCUGUGAUAUUUUCACACUGGUAAAUGUUACCUCUAUUUUAAUUACUGCUAUAAAUAGGUUUAUAUUAUUGAUUCACUUACUGACUUUGCAUUUUCGUUUUUAAAAGGAUGUAUAAAUUUUUACCUGUUUAAAUAAAAUUUAAUUUCAAAUGUAGUGGUGGGGCUUCUUUCUAUUUUUGAUGCACUGAAUUUUUGUGUAAUAAAGAACAUAAUUGGGCUCUAAGCCAUAA